GCCCCCGCCGGUUCGCGUCUCUCUGCUGCGGCGCGGGGACCGCUGUGCUCUCGGUAGGCGGCUGGGCUGGGUGGGCUCCGCACUUCCUUCCCGCUCCGUGCCGCGCGUCCCGGCACCCUUAGGCCCACUCCGGGAGGGGUCUGCGUCCUGGGCCCGCCUGCCGGCUGUUCCGUGUCCCGCCGUGCCCGUCGCGGGCGGCCUCGCGCCUGUUCCGCUGCAGGUUGGCCCCGGCGGCGGGAGCGCCCCCGAUCCGGACAAAGAAACGAGCGCUCGGAAACGGGGUCUCUGGGGGAUCCAGUGACGUGCCCAACCACAGAGACCAGACCCCUCCUCCUGUAGAGAGUGGUGCUGCCCUCUCGGGAUGUACCUGCAGGUGGAGACCCGCACCAGCUCCCGCCUCCAUCUGAAGAGGGCUCCAGGCAUCCGGUCCUGGUCCCUGCUGGUUGGAAUCUUGUCGAUUGGCCUGGCUGCUGCCUACUACAGCGGAGAUAGCCUGGGCUGGAAGCUCUUCUACGUCACAGGCUGCCUGUUUGUGGCUGUGCAGAACUUGGAGGACUGGGAGGAAGCCAUCUUCGACAAGAGCACAGGGAAGGUUGUUUUGAAGACGUUCAGCCUCUACAAGAAGCUGCUGACUCUUUUCAGAGCUGGCCACGACCAGGUGGUGGUCCUGCUCCAUGAUGUCCGUGAUGUGAGCGUGGAGGAGGAGAAGGUCCGGUACUUCGGGAAAGGCUACAUGGUGGUGCUCCGGCUUGCGACGGGCUUCUCCCACCCCCUCACGCAGAGUGCAGUCAUGGGCCACCGCAGUGAUGUGGAAGCCAUCGCCAAGCUCAUCACCAGCUUCCUGGAGCUGCACUGCCUUGAGAGCCCCACAGAGCUGUCUCAGAGCAGCGACAGUGAGGCCGGUGACCCUGCAAGCCAGAGCUGACAGCCCCACUGUGCCUGAGCCCGUGCACCGCCCACAGGACCCAUGGCACAUUCCCGGUGUGCCUGAGCCCGUGCACCGCCCACAGGACCCGUGGCACAUUCCCGGUGUGCCUGAGCCCGUGCACCGCCCACAGGACCCGUGGCACAUUCCCGGUGUGCCUGAGCCCGUGCACCGCCCACAGGACCCGUGGCACAUUCCCGGUGUGCCUGAGCCCGUGCACCGCCCACAGGACCCGUGGCCUUGGCUUCAGUUGGUGCCUCCAGCCGAGUUGGCCUAUUGCCUGCUCAUGCUGCUGCUUGCACACUGCAUGAAACAGCAGGCCAGACCAGGACAUCCAGACUUUCUCCAUCGUGAGGCCUGGGCCUGCCUUUCUGCAGCCGGAGGUCUCGCCAGCCCUGGACUCCUGCUUUGGGCCACAGCAAGACCUCGGGCGAGUGGAGAGGCGGGGCCAGGCCGGGCCCUUGUGGGUGCUGAUGCUGCAUGUUGUCCCCGACACAGCGUCCUCUCCCUGGUGGACAUCCCCAGCGGUCAGGUGCUUCCCCAAGGGCAGUGAGGGGUGAACAUCCAGGGCCUACCUGGCUGUGCACGCUGCAGCCACACUGUGGAAGCUGCCCCUCCCCGAGGACCCGCCUCCCUUGCUGAUGCCAGGAUCUCGGCGCAUAGACCACUCUGCCCCAGCGGUCGUCACAGAAAGGUCUCUCUGUUCCUCACACUCAGCUUCAGCAUAAGCUGUGAGGCCAGAAAAAAGGUCAGCUCUUCUAGUAUCGUGCAGUGCUUAAAAACCGGGAGCUCCAGCCGGGCGCAGUGGUUCAUGCCAGUAAUCCCAGCACUUUCGGAGGCCGAGGUGGGAGGAUUGCUUGAGGCCAGGAGUUCAAGACCAGCCUGGGCAACACAGCAAGAUCCUGUCUUUGUAAAAAAACUAACCAAACAGGAAAAACUGGGAGAUUUUCUGCAGAAAUUGAGUUCCAGCCUCUCUCGAACCUGGGAAGACCUGGCAGGAGGGGGCUGGGCUCUCGGCUACAGACUUCUCCCCACCCCGUAGGAGCUGAACGCCAACCAUCCUGACCCGCCAGUGCUCUUGGUCUCCUGAGUGUACCCAGGUCCUCCCAGGUGCGGUGUGCACCGAGCGCGCCUGGCCUGAUGCCCUGGCCUGUGAGCUGGGGACUCCUGGGCCCUGUGAGCCCCUAGGCGGCAGGCCCAGGAAUGGCUGGGUAGGACAGGGAACACCUUUGCCCCACGUCUGGCUGUGACCUCGGUGAAAGCCGACAGGAGAGAGAUGGGACCCUCCUCCUCAGUAGUGGCUGCCAGUCCCUCGUUGCAGGACAGGGUCAUCAUAACCAUAAAUAACCCUUCACGUGUCACCUGCAGCUUCCACUCUUUAUUUCCAAAGAAUCAGUGUCACACAUGCAGAUCACAAA